AGCCGUUUCCGGAGUCUGCGCUGCGCCCGGUUCCGCCAUUGCGGCUCUCCUGGCCCCUGGAGCCUCCGCCCCCGACCCGAGCUCUUUCGUCUGCCUGCCAGUUUCCUGCGUCCCCGGAGAGGAUCCUGCUGAGCCCAGCCUCCCCCCUCCCCUUCUCCUCCUCUCCCUUGGAGAGCCCGGGCAGCCACUGCCCCGCAGCCCCAGUGACAGGAGGAGACCAUAACCCCCGACAGCGCCAUGGCCCAGAUUCUGCCAAUUCGUUUUCAGGAGCAUCUCCAGCUCCAGAACCUGGGUAUCAACCCAGCAAACAUUGGCUUCAGUACCCUGACUAUGGAGUCUGACAAAUUCAUCUGCAUUAGAGAAAAAGUAGGAGAGCAGGCCCAGGUGGUAAUCAUUGAUAUGAAUGACCCAAGUAAUCCAAUUCGAAGACCAAUUUCAGCAGACAGCGCCAUCAUGAAUCCAGCUAGCAAAGUAAUUGCACUGAAAGGUAUAAAAGAAUCUGGGAAAACUCUUCAGAUUUUUAACAUUGAAAUGAAAAGUAAAAUGAAGGCUCAUACCAUGACUGAUGAUGUCACCUUUUGGAAAUGGAUCUCUUUGAAUACGGUUGCUCUUGUUACGGAUAAUGCAGUUUAUCACUGGAGUAUGGAAGGAGAGUCUCAGCCAGUGAAAAUGUUUGAUCGCCAUUCUAGCCUUGCAGGGUGCCAGAUUAUCAAUUACCGUACAGAUGCAAAACAAAAGUGGUUACUUCUGACUGGUAUAUCUGCACAGCAAAAUCGUGUGGUGGGAGCUAUGCAGCUAUAUUCUGUAGAUAGGAAAGUGUCUCAGCCCAUUGAAGGACAUGCAGCUAGCUUUGCACAGUUUAAGAUGGAAGGAAAUGCAGAAGAAUCAACGUUAUUUUGUUUUGCAGUUCGGGGCCAAGCUGGAGGGAAGUUACAUAUUAUUGAAGUUGGCACACCACCUACAGGGAACCAGCCCUUUCCAAAGAAGGCAGUGGAUGUCUUCUUUCCUCCAGAAGCACAAAAUGAUUUUCCUGUUGCAAUGCAGAUCAGUGAAAAGCAUGAUGUGGUGUUCUUGAUAACCAAGUAUGGUUAUAUCCACCUCUAUGAUCUUGAGACUGGUACCUGCAUCUACAUGAAUAGAAUCAGUGGAGAAACAAUUUUUGUUACUGCACCUCAUGAAGCCACAGCUGGAAUAAUUGGAGUAAACAGAAAGGGACAAGUUCUGUCAGUGUGUGUGGAAGAAGAAAACAUAAUUCCUUACAUCACCAAUGUUCUACAAAAUCCUGAUUUGGCUCUGAGAAUGGCUGUACGUAAUAACUUAGCCGGUGCUGAAGAACUCUUUGCCCGGAAAUUUAAUGCUCUUUUUGCCCAGGGAAAUUACUCGGAGGCAGCAAAGGUGGCUGCUAAUGCACCAAAGGGAAUUCUUCGUACUCCAGACACUAUCCGUCGGUUCCAGAGUGUCCCAGCCCAGCCAGGUCAAACUUCUCCUCUACUUCAGUACUUUGGUAUCCUUUUGGACCAGGGACAGCUCAACAAAUACGAAUCCUUAGAGCUUUGUAGGCCUGUACUUCAGCAAGGGCGAAAACAGCUUUUGGAGAAAUGGUUAAAAGAAGAUAAGCUGGAAUGUUCUGAAGAACUGGGUGAUCUUGUGAAAUCUGUGGACCCUACAUUGGCACUUAGUGUGUACCUAAGGGCUAACGUCCCAAAUAAAGUCAUUCAGUGCUUUGCAGAAACAGGUCAAGUCCAAAAGAUUGUUUUAUAUGCUAAAAAAGUUGGAUACACUCCAGAUUGGAUAUUUCUGCUGAGAAAUGUAAUGCGAAUCAGUCCAGAUCAGGGACAGCAGUUUGCCCAAAUGUUAGUUCAAGAUGAAGAGCCUCUUGCUGACAUCACACAGAUUGUAGAUGUCUUUAUGGAAUACAAUCUAAUUCAGCAGUGUACUGCAUUCUUGCUUGAUGCUCUGAAGAAUAAUCGCCCAUCUGAAGGUCCUUUACAGACGCGGUUACUUGAGAUGAACCUUAUGCAUGCGCCUCAAGUUGCAGAUGCUAUUCUAGGCAAUCAGAUGUUCACACAUUAUGACCGGGCUCAUAUUGCUCAACUGUGUGAAAAGGCUGGCCUACUGCAGCGUGCAUUAGAACAUUUCACUGAUUUAUAUGAUAUAAAACGUGCAGUGGUUCACACCCAUCUUCUUAACCCUGAGUGGUUAGUCAACUACUUUGGUUCCUUAUCAGUAGAAGACUCCCUAGAAUGUCUCAGAGCCAUGCUGUCUGCCAACAUCCGUCAGAAUCUGCAGAUUUGUGUUCAGGUGGCUUCUAAAUAUCAUGAACAACUGUCAACUCAGUCUCUGAUUGAACUUUUUGAAUCUUUCAAGAGUUUUGAAGGUCUCUUUUAUUUUCUGGGAUCCAUUGUUAACUUUAGCCAGGACCCAGAUGUGCACUUUAAAUAUAUUCAGGCAGCUUGCAAGACUGGGCAAAUCAAAGAAGUAGAAAGAAUCUGUAGAGAAAGCAACUGCUACGAUCCUGAGCGAGUCAAGAAUUUUCUUAAGGAAGCAAAACUAACAGAUCAGCUACCACUUAUCAUUGUGUGUGAUCGAUUUGACUUUGUCCAUGAUUUGGUGCUCUAUUUAUAUAGAAAUAAUCUUCAAAAGUAUAUAGAGAUAUAUGUACAGAAGGUGAAUCCAAGUCGACUUCCUGUAGUUAUUGGAGGAUUACUUGAUGUUGACUGUUCUGAAGAUGUCAUAAAAAACUUGAUUCUUGUUGUAAGAGGUCAAUUCUCUACUGAUGAGCUUGUUGCUGAGGUUGAAAAAAGAAACAGAUUGAAACUGCUUCUGCCUUGGCUAGAGGCCAGAAUUCAUGAGGGCUGUGAGGAGCCUGCUACUCACAAUGCCUUAGCCAAAAUCUACAUAGACAGUAAUAACAACCCGGAGAGAUUUCUUCGUGAAAAUCCCUACUAUGACAGUCGCGUUGUUGGAAAGUAUUGUGAGAAGAGAGAUCCACAUCUGGCCUGUGUUGCUUAUGAACGUGGCCAAUGUGAUCUGGAACUUAUUAAUGUUUGCAAUGAGAAUUCCCUCUUCAAAAGUCUUUCUCGCUACCUGGUACGUCGAAAGGAUCCAGAAUUGUGGGGCAGCGUGCUGCUGGAAAGCAAUCCUUACAGGAGACCCCUAAUUGACCAGGUUGUACAAACAGCUUUGUCUGAGACUCAGGACCCUGAAGAAGUGUCAGUAACUGUAAAGGCUUUCAUGACUGCAGACCUUCCUAAUGAACUCAUUGAACUGCUGGAGAAAAUUGUCCUUGAUAACUCUGUAUUCAGUGAACACAGGAAUCUGCAAAACCUCCUUAUCCUCACUGCAAUUAAGGCUGACCGUACACGUGUUAUGGAGUAUAUUAACCGCCUGGAUAAUUAUGAUGCCCCAGAUAUUGCCAAUAUCGCCAUCAGCAAUGAGCUGUUUGAAGAAGCAUUUGCCAUUUUCCGGAAAUUUGAUGUCAAUACUUCAGCAGUUCAGGUCUUAAUUGAGCAUAUUGGAAACUUGGAUCGGGCAUAUGAGUUUGCUGAACGUUGCAAUGAACCUGCGGUCUGGAGUCAACUUGCAAAAGCCCAGUUGCAGAAAGGAAUGGUGAAAGAAGCCAUUGAUUCUUAUAUCAAAGCAGAUGAUCCUUCCUCCUACAUGGAAGUUGUUCAGGCUGCCAAUACUAGUGGAAACUGGGAAGAACUGGUGAAGUACUUGCAGAUGGCCCGUAAGAAGGCUCGAGAGUCCUAUGUGGAGACAGAACUGAUAUUCGCACUGGCUAAAACAAACCGCCUUGCAGAGUUAGAAGAAUUUAUCAAUGGACCAAAUAAUGCUCAUAUCCAACAAGUUGGUGACCGUUGUUAUGAUGAAAAAAUGUAUGAUGCUGCUAAGUUGUUGUACAAUAAUGUUUCCAAUUUUGGACGUUUGGCAUCUACCCUGGUUCACCUGGGUGAAUAUCAGGCAGCUGUUGAUGGGGCUAGGAAAGCUAACAGUACUCGAACAUGGAAAGAGGUCUGCUUCGCCUGUGUAGAUGGGAAAGAAUUCCGUCUUGCUCAGAUGUGUGGACUUCAUAUUGUUGUACAUGCAGAUGAAUUAGAAGAACUUAUCAACUACUAUCAGGAUCGUGGCUAUUUUGAAGAGCUGAUCACCAUGUUGGAAGCAGCACUGGGACUUGAGCGAGCUCACAUGGGAAUGUUUACUGAAUUAGCUAUUCUAUACUCUAAAUUUAAGCCUCAGAAAAUGAGGGAGCACCUGGAGCUGUUCUGGUCUAGAGUGAAUAUUCCCAAGGUGCUAAGAGCUGCAGAACAAGCUCAUCUUUGGGCAGAACUGGUGUUUUUGUAUGACAAGUAUGAAGAAUAUGAUAAUGCCAUAAUUACCAUGAUGAAUCAUCCAACUGAUGCCUGGAAAGAAGGGCAAUUCAAAGAUAUCAUUACCAAGGUUGCCAAUGUGGAACUAUACUACAGAGCAAUACAGUUCUACUUAGAAUUCAAGCCUCUGUUGUUAAAUGAUUUGCUGAUGGUGCUGUCUCCACGGUUGGAUCACACUCGUGCAGUCAAUUAUUUCAGCAAGGUUAAACAGCUACCACUGGUGAAACCGUAUUUGCGUUCAGUUCAGAACCAUAACAACAAAUCUGUGAAUGAAUCAUUGAACAAUCUUUUUAUUACAGAAGAAGAUUAUCAGGCUCUGCGAACAUCAAUAGAUGCUUAUGACAACUUUGACAAUAUCUCGCUUGCUCAGCGUUUGGAAAAACAUGAACUCAUUGAGUUCAGGAGAAUUGCUGCUUAUCUCUUCAAAGGCAACAAUCGCUGGAAACAGAGUGUAGAGCUGUGCAAGAAAGACAGCCUUUACAAGGAUGCAAUGCAGUAUGCUUCUGAAUCUAAAGAUACUGAAUUGGCUGAAGAACUCCUGCAGUGGUUUUUGCAGGAAGAAAAAAGAGAGUGCUUUGGAGCUUGUCUGUUUACCUGUUACGAUCUUUUAAGGCCAGAUGUCGUCCUAGAAACUGCAUGGAGGCACAAUAUCAUGGAUUUUGCCAUGCCCUAUUUCAUCCAGGUCAUGAAGGAGUACUUGACAAAGGUGGAUAAAUUAGAUGCUUCAGAAUCACUGAGAAAAGAAGAAGAACAAGCUACAGAGACACAACCCAUUGUUUAUGGUCAGCCCCAGUUGAUGCUGACAGCAGGACCCAGUGUUGCCGUCCCUCCCCAGGCACCUUUUGGUUAUGGUUAUACCGCACCACCGUAUGGACAGCCACAGCCUGGCUUUGGGUACAGCAUGUGAGAUGAAGCGCUGAUCCUGUAGUCACCUAUUUUCGUACUGAAACAUCGUCUUUACCCACUUCUCAGUUUAUAAUGGGGGAAAACAGGCAACGUGUUCUUGUAACCUUUAUUUCAUGAAGGACUUCUUUUUGUUUCUAACUAUAAACUUGGAUCACCUAUGUUAAAACCUUAUUUCACAUUCCACAUCAUUUUAGAAUUUAUUUUCGAAGGGGAAUAGUUUCAAUGUUUUAUUCACUUGGGCUUUUUUUCUUCCCCCUCUUUCUUUAAAGAACUGCUCAAUAUUCAAUCUGUUGUGAAGAACCUGAUUUGCACUCUGUAGUGUUUAAAGAAACAAAGAAACUCUAAUAUUGAAUCUCUUAAAUUUAGUGUAUGUAAACAGCUUACAAAUACGUAUUGUCUAAAUGCAUUUAAAUCUGUUUUAUUCAAAGAAAAGCUAAAGCAAAAACACUGGCAUAUGACCAUGCAAGACUGUCAGUGCCAACAAAGACAACACUAAUCAGCACAUCGUACACUGGAUUGCAGUGCUUCCCAGAUUAUUGAAAAAUGUUACAGACAACUUGCCUGAUUUUUAAAUGAGCGUAAAAGGCCCUCUAACCUAUGCAGGUUUCCCCAUUAUGCAUAUAGAAAAUGCUAGUAUGUUUUGCUCACUUCAUAUGUAACAGGUGCCCUUAUGUUGUGCUGUAUCCUGUGCUUUUUCUGUGGGACCAUUCCAUUCAGGAGCAAAGAGCACCAUGAUUCCAAUCUUGUGUGUGUUUACUAACCCUUCCCUGAGGUUUGUGUAUGUUGGAUAUUGUGGUGUUUUAGAUCACUGAGUGUACAGAAGAGAGAAAUUCAAACAAAAUAUUGCUGUUCUUCAGUUUUGUUUGUGGAAUUUGAAAUUACUCAAAUUUAAAAUAAAUUACUGGACUGUGGAAAUAACAUAGAAUUGAAGUUUUAAUUAAAUACCACUCAAACGAAAAGAACAGUAGUUUUUGUAGUUUUAUAUUGGAUACUGAGGCAUUAGGGAGGCAUGAAAGGAAGAGGAAUGAGGAUUGAGACAUGUGAAGACAUUGUGCAUUAUAUCAAUGUGCAUUCCUGUAGUUCAUUAACAAGGUACAUGCAAUAGUCUAAAGAACCAGAGUCACUACUAUAGUGGCUUAACAUUUAAUCUGUCUCCAAUAUUUUAACCAAGUGACACCGAGGUUUUUAUCGAAGCAUUUCACUUAAAUGAACAAAUCAUGGCUGUUAUAUUAACUUGAAAUAAAAUAUAUUUAAACAUGUAGUUAACAUGCUCUUUCUCAUCAUGAAUUAUAAAGGUGCCCAAAUUAUGGGUAUCUUGAUUUUUUUCAAAAAUUGGUUGUGUGAAUCCAGCUCUUGCUUAUGGCUGAGAAUGUUCCUAAAGUUCAUUUCACUAUCCCUUAAUCCUCAAUAGCUACACAUACCCCCUUGCCUAGUUAGUCUUGCACUGCUUUACAACUCUCUUAGGCAAAUUACCUAACAUAAGCUCCACAGAAGAGUUUUUUAAAACUUAAAAUCCCUGUCCCACCAGGUGUGGUGGCUCAUGCCUGUAAUCCCAGCACUUUGGGAGGCUGAGGCAGGCGGAUUGCUUGAGGCCAGGAGUUCGAGACAAGCCUGACCAACAUGGUGACUCCAUCUCUACUAAAAAUAAAAAAUCAGCCAGGUGUGAUGGUGGAUGCCUAUAAGAUCCUAGCUGCUACUCAGGAGGCAGGAGGCUGAGGCAUGAGAAUCACUUGAACCUGUGAGGCAAAGGUUGUAGUGAGCCAAGAUCACGUCACUGCACUCCAUCCUGGGUGACAGAAUGAGACUCUUGUCUCAAAAAACAAAAAAACCUAUUUAGUUUCAUCCAGGACAUUAAGUGAAAGUGUUUAAUGUGAGUGCAGGUCAGUGAAGAAUACAAUGGUGCCCCUGCUUUGAUUUGUGGGAGGUGCCAUCAGUUUUCCCCACCACUGCUUUUGCACCCUCAGUGCAAAUAUCAACACAGAGAAAAAAAAAAUAAUAAUAGUAUUAUGAAAACAUUGACUCUGUGGAGACCCUGUGGGUUCUGCAGAGUAUACUUUGAAAACUAUAAGAUUAUGAGUUCUAUAAAAUACCAAGUACAGAUGAACUAGAAAACAAGCAUAUAUCCACAAUUACCAGAAUUUUCAUAGUAUUCCUUUUAGUAGAUAUGCCAUGACAGUUACUUAGCCACCCCAUGCCAUCCUGUUGGGAAUGCCACUACCUUUGAAUUUGGAGCCAUCAGUCUAUCUGAGGCAAACCUCAGAAAUUACCUGAGCCAGAAUCAUGCACUUAGCACUGAGUUCAACUCAGUCUUAACGUUGCAUUUUGUUGCAUCACUUUUGCAGCCAGUAAACAUUCUGUUUAGAAAUAGUUGCUAUUGUGGCAUCAUUCACAGUUGCAAUUUUUCUCCUGUGCUGUCAUAUGCCUGUGCGAAGUGUAUUAAAUGAAUCAAAUAUUAGAAAUUUCAAGGCUGUCUUUAGUGUUCUGCCCACAAUACUCCACCAAUGACCUUAGACCUUGAGAUGGUGCUAUAACGCUGCUUAUAUUGCAGUUAACCAUAGAGAGGUGGAGCCACUUAAAAUGGGCCUAUUACCAAAAUUCUCCCUGGCAUCAUUACAGUUCUUGGGGAUACACUGAUUUUAGAAAUUACUGUCAGUAUCCUCCUAAAAGAAGGCUUAAAUAGUUUCUAACAAGAUGACUAUCAGGAAGCUAUGUGGCUUGGGGAGUUGGGACCCUCUGCCUCAUAUUCUGGGUAACUGGUAUAACAUAGUAAUUAUUAGGAUUGUAUCAAGUGUAUCUAAAGAUCAAAAGGGAAAAAAGGCACCCUUAAUUGUCAAAGUUAGUUCUAGGAAAAAAUACUAGCAGGGAUGACAAACUACGUUCACUUUACAGUUACCAUAAAUUCUUACUUGGGCCCACCCAUUUCCAUCUGUUAAGGUCCAUAAGGUUACUCAAGUUUCAGUGGCUUCAUUGUUACAAGAAAGGGGGGAAGUGAGAAACUUUAAUAGGCUGUGAUUUAGAACCACUGCUGAUUAACCUUUGGCCAGUAUGGGUCAGGGAAGGUGAACAUGAAACACUGCACAGUAGGUUGUAUCAAUGCUAUAAAAC